AAACAAUCUCGAUUCUAAAUUGAAACGAACGCAGCAUUUCAGGGACUGGAUGAGGAGCUUACGGUUUUUUACAGAAUCAUCAAUAUCUUGGAAGAAAAAGAAUGUUAAGAAAUAACAAAACAAUAAUUAUUAAGUACUUUCUUAAUCUCAUUAAUGGAGCUUUCUUGGUUCUUGGACUUUUAUUCAUGGGAUUUGGUGCAUGGCUCUUAUUAGAUAGAAAUAAUUUUUUAACAGCUUUUGAUGAAAAUAAUCACUUCAUAGUACCUAUUUCUCAAAUUUUGAUUGGAAUGGGAUCUUCUACUGUUCUUUUUUGUCUAUUGGGUUAUAUAGGAAUUCACAACGAAAUCAGAUGGCUCCUAAUUGUGUAUGCAGUAUUGAUAACAUGGACCUUUGCUGUUCAGGUUGUACUUUCAGCAUUCAUCAUCACAAAGAAAGAGGAGGUUCAGCAACUAUGGCAUGACAAAAUUGAUUUUGUCAUUUCUGAGUAUGGAUCUAAAGAUAAGCCUGAAGAUAUAACCAAGUGGACUAUUCUGAAUGCCUUACAGAAAACAUUACAGUGUUGUGGCCAACAUAAUUACACAGACUGGAUAAAGAAUAAGAACAAAGAAAAUUCAGGACAGGUGCCAUGUUCUUGCACAAAGUCAACUUUAAGAAAAUGGUUUUGUGAUGAGCCACUGAAUGCAACUUACCUUGAGCCUUCCUUGAGAAGUCCUGCAGAAAGAGGAGGCACUUCUGUCAAAGCCUUGGUGCAUAAGAUUGGAAAGGGAGCUAAAACACCAGGAGUAAAAGAAUAGGCAAAAACUAAAGGGAGUGGACCCCAGCAAUGAUGAAUGUGGUGUUCAAGUAAGUGUAGCAGAAGCAAGAGUAAAGGGUUGUCUGGAGCAACUGCGAUUUACAGGUGUGGGAUACUGAUAACUAGAUUUUUUCAUCCUAAGAACUGCGAAUACUUUGUAUAGUUUACAUAUUAAGCUUAUUCUAAUCUUAAGAUGUAUUGUUUCAAUUGCAUAAUUAAUUCAUAAAUAAAUGGAACAUUACUUUUUUUUUUUAAAAAAAAGCAUCUACUCUUUGGGAAAUAACCAUUUUAUGUGGUGAUAUAUACAGUAGUUGCCCCUAUCUGCAGUUUCACAUUGUGAGAGUUCAACCAUUGAAAAUAUUAAGUGGAAAAUUCCAGAAAUAAACAAUUCAUAAGUUUUCAAUUGCACACUGUUCUGGGUAGUAUGAUGAAAUCUUGUGUCUUCCUGCCCUGUUCCCUCCUGGGACAUGAGUCAUCCCUUUGUCCAGUGUAUUCAUGAUGCAGAUGCUACCCACCCUUAGUCACUUAGUAGUCAUCUUCAUUGUAAGAUCGACUGUUGAGGUAUCACAGUGCCUGUGUUCAAGAACCCUUAAUUUACUUAAUGAUGACCCCAAAGUGUAAGAAUAGUGAUGCUGGCAUAUUGUUAUAAUUGUUCUAUUUUAUUAUUAGUUAUUGUUUUAAUCUCUUGUUGUGCCUAAUUUAUAAAUUAAACUCUAUUAUAUAUAUGUUUCUAUAGGAAGACAUGUAAUAUAUUUAGGGUUUGAUACUGUCUGUGUUUUCAGGCCUCCACUGGGGGUAUUGCUGGUGGGUAAGUAGGGAAACUACUGUAUCCUGAUGAAUUACAAUAGUCUGCAGAAGAGAAAAUCUCUUUCUAAAGUGUAACAAAUUUCUGAUUUUAAUUACAUGAUAACAUCUUAGCAAUUUUAAAAUUAGCAACUGAGGUGUCCUGCUGCCGUAGAAAGCUUUCUGGACUAAAAGUCCAGUUCGCCAAUUAGAUAUUGACUUACUAUUUAGACUUUGGUAAAUUACUAAUCUCUGUUUACCUUUUAUUUUUUGUAAAGAUUUAUGUAUAAGAUCAUUUCCAUCUCCAUGUCCAUCUGAAUAACUUCUUUUUCUUAGGGUUGUGAAAAUAAAAUCAGUGCAUGGUAUAAUGUUAAUGUGUUAACCUUAAUCGGAAUUAACUUUGGACUUUUAACUUC